AGACGGGCGGCCGCGCGGGAGUGUGUGCGCCGGGAGCUGGCUGAGGGACUGCAAGGCGGCCGGCGGCGACCAUGGCAGCGGGCCGGCGGCGGCCGUAGUGGCCCAGGCCUGGGCUUCAGCCUCCCGGGGCCCCAGAGGGCGGGGCGGUCCGGGCCGCGGCGGUGGCGGCGCCACUUCCCUGCUCCCGCCCGAGGACUCCUGCGGGCACUCGCUGAGGACCAGCGGACCGGCGGCGCGAAUCUGACUGAGGGGCGGGGACGCCGUCUGUUCCCCGCCGCUCCCGGCAGGGCCGGGCCGGGCUGGGCCGGGCUGGGCCGGGCGGGCCCCUGGGAGCAGCCCCCAGGCGGGGGACCGCCUUGGAGACCCGAAGCCGGAGCUAGAGGCAGGCGGUGGGCCCGGGUGGAGUCCCGGCCGGAGCUGGUGGUUCGGGGGCGGUGCUAGGCCCCGAGGCUGCGGGACCUGAGCGCGAGGAGCCUGAGUGCGGGUCCAGCGGUGGCGGCAUGAGCCGGCCCCCGCCGACGGGGAAAAUGCCCGGCGCCCCCGAGACCGCGCCGGGGGACGGGGCAGGCGCGAGCCGCCAGAGGAAGCUGGAGGCGCUGAUCCGAGACCCUCGCUCCCCCAUCAACGUGGAGAGCUUGCUGGAUGGCUUAAAUUCCUUGGUCCUUGAUUUAGAUUUUCCUGCUUUGAGGAAAAACAAGAACAUAGAUAAUUUCUUAAAUAGAUAUGAGAAAAUUGUGAAAAAAAUCAGAGGUCUACAGAUGAAGGCAGAAGACUAUGAUGUUGUAAAAGUUAUUGGAAGAGGUGCUUUUGGUGAAGUGCAGUUGGUUCGUCACAAGGCAUCGCAGAAGGUUUAUGCUAUGAAGCUUCUUAGUAAGUUUGAAAUGAUAAAAAGAUCAGAUUCUGCCUUUUUUUGGGAAGAAAGAGAUAUUAUGGCCUUUGCCAAUAGCCCCUGGGUGGUUCAGCUUUUUUAUGCCUUUCAAGAUGAUAGGUAUCUGUACAUGGUAAUGGAGUACAUGCCUGGUGGAGACCUUGUAAACCUUAUGAGUAAUUAUGAUGUGCCUGAAAAAUGGGCCAAAUUUUACACUGCUGAAGUUGUUCUUGCUCUGGAUGCAAUACACUCCAUGGGUUUAAUACACAGAGAUGUGAAGCCUGACAACAUGCUCUUGGAUAAACAUGGACAUCUAAAAUUAGCAGAUUUUGGCACGUGUAUGAAGAUGGAUGAAACAGGCAUGGUACAUUGUGAUACAGCAGUUGGAACACCGGAUUAUAUAUCACCUGAGGUUCUGAAAUCACAAGGGGGUGAUGGUUUCUAUGGGCGAGAAUGUGAUUGGUGGUCUGUAGGUGUUUUCCUUUAUGAGAUGCUAGUGGGGGAUACUCCAUUUUAUGCGGAUUCACUUGUAGGAACAUAUAGCAAAAUUAUGGAUCAUAAGAAUUCACUGUGUUUCCCUGAAGAUGCAGAAAUUUCCAAACAUGCAAAGAAUCUCAUCUGUGCUUUCUUAACAGAUAGGGAGGUACGACUUGGGAGAAAUGGGGUGGAAGAAAUCAGACAGCAUCCUUUCUUUAAGAAUGAUCAGUGGCAUUGGGAUAACAUAAGAGAAACGGCAGCUCCUGUAGUACCUGAACUCAGCAGUGACAUAGACAGCAGCAAUUUCGAUGACAUUGAAGAUGACAAAGGAGAUGUAGAAACCUUCCCAAUUCCUAAAGCUUUUGUUGGAAAUCAGCUGCCUUUCAUCGGAUUUACCUACUAUAGAGAAAAUUUAUUAUUAAGUGACUCUCCAUCUUGUAGAGAAACUGAUUCCAUACAAUCAAGGAAAAAUGAAGAAAGUCAAGAGAUUCAGAAAAAACUGUAUACAUUAGAAGAACAUCUUAGCAAUGAGAUGCAAGCCAAAGAGGAACUGGAACAGAAGUGCAAAUCUGUUAAUACUCGCCUAGAAAAAACAGCAAAGGAGCUAGAAGAGGAGAUUACCUUACGGAAAAGUGUGGAAUCAGCAUUAAGACAGUUAGAAAGAGAAAAGGCGCUUCUUCAGCACAAAAAUGCAGAAUAUCAGAGGAAAGCUGAUCAUGAAGCAGACAAAAAACGAAAUUUGGAAAAUGAUGUUAACAGCUUAAAAGAUCAACUUGAAGAUUUGAAAAAAAGAAAUCAAAACUCUCAAAUAUCCACUGAGAAAGUGAAUCAACUCCAGAGACAACUGGAUGAAACCAAUGCUUUACUGCGAACAGAGUCUGAUACUGCAGCCCGGUUAAGGAAAACCCAGGCAGAAAGUUCAAAACAGAUUCAGCAGCUGGAAUCUAACAAUAGAGAUCUACAAGAUAAAAACUGCCUGCUGGAGACUGCCAAGUUAAAACUUGAAAAGGAAUUUAUCAAUCUUCAGUCAGCUCUAGAAUCUGAAAGGAGGGAUCGAACCCAUGGAUCAGAGAUAAUUAAUGAUUUACAAGGUAGAAUAUGUGGCCUAGAAGAAGAUUUAAAGAACGGCAAAAUCUUACUAGCGAAAGUAGAACUGGAGAAGAGACAACUUCAGGAGAGAUUUACUGAUUUGGAAAAGGAAAAAAGCAACAUGGAAAUAGAUAUGACAUACCAACUAAAAGUUAUACAGCAGAGCCUAGAACAAGAAGAAGCUGAACAUAAGGCCACAAAGGCACGACUAGCAGAUAAAAAUAAGAUCUAUGAGUCCAUCGAAGAAGCCAAAUCAGAAGCCAUGAAAGAAAUGGAGAAGAAGCUCUUGGAGGAAAGAACUUUAAAACAGAAAGUGGAGAACCUAUUGCUAGAAGCUGAGAAAAGAUGUUCUCUAUUAGACUGUGACCUCAAACAGUCACAGCAGAAAAUAAAUGAGCUCCUUAAACAGAAAGAUGUGCUAAAUGAGGAUGUUAGAAACCUGACAUUAAAAAUAGAGCAAGAAACUCAGAAGCGCUGCCUUACACAAAAUGACCUGAAGAUGCAAACACAACAGGUUAACACACUAAAAAUGUCAGAAAAGCAGUUAAAGCAAGAAAAUAACCAUCUCAUGGAAAUGAAAAUGAACUUGGAAAAACAAAAUGCUGAACUUCGAAAAGAACGUCAGGAUGCAGAUGGGCAAAUGAAAGAGCUCCAGGAUCAGCUCGAAGCAGAACAGUAUUUCUCAACCCUUUAUAAAACACAAGUUAGGGAGCUUAAAGAAGAAUGUGAAGAAAAGACCAAACUUGGUAAAGAAUUGCAGCAGAAGAAACAGGAAUUACAGGAUGAACGGGACUCUUUGGCUGCCCAACUGGAGAUCACCUUGACCAAAGCAGAUUCUGAGCAACUGGCUCGUUCAAUUGCUGAAGAACAAUAUUCUGAUUUGGAAAAAGAGAAGAUCAUGAAAGAGCUGGAGAUCAAAGAGAUGAUGGCUAGACACAAACAGGAACUUACGGAAAAAGAUGCUACAAUUGCUUCUCUUGAGGAAACUAAUAGGACACUAACUAGUGAUGUUGCCAAUCUUGCAAAUGAGAAAGAAGAAUUAAAUAACAAAUUGAAAGAUGUUCAAGAGCAACUGUCAAGAUUGAAAGAUGAAGAAAUAAGCGCAGCAGCUAUUAAAGCACAGUUUGAGAAGCAGCUAUUAACAGAAAGAACACUCAAAACUCAAGCUGUGAAUAAGUUGGCUGAGAUCAUGAAUCGAAAAGAACCUGUCAAGCGUGGUAAUGACACAGAUGUGCGGAGAAAAGAGAAGGAGAAUAGAAAGCUACAUAUGGAGCUUAAAUCUGAACGUGAGAAAUUGACCCAGCAGAUGAUCAAGUAUCAGAAAGAACUGAAUGAAAUGCAGGCACAAAUAGCUGAAGAGAGCCAGAUUCGAAUUGAACUGCAGAUGACAUUGGACAGUAAAGACAGUGACAUUGAGCAGCUGCGGUCACAACUCCAAGCCUUGCAUAUUGGUCUGGAUAGUUCCAGUAUAGGCAGUGGACCAGGGGAUGCUGAGGCAGAUGAUGGGUUUCCAGAAUCAAGAUUAGAAGGAUGGCUUUCAUUGCCUGUACGAAACAACACUAAGAAAUUUGGAUGGGUUAAAAAGUAUGUGAUUGUAAGCAGUAAGAAGAUUCUUUUCUAUGACAGUGAACAAGAUAAAGAACAAUCCAAUCCUUACAUGGUUUUAGAUAUAGACAAGUUAUUUCAUGUCCGACCAGUUACACAGACAGAUGUGUAUAGAGCAGAUGCUAAAGAAAUUCCAAGGAUAUUCCAGAUUCUGUAUGCCAAUGAAGGAGAAAGUAAGAAGGAACAAGAAUUUCCAGUGGAGCCAGUUGGAGAAAAAUCUAAUUAUAUUUGCCACAAGGGACAUGAGUUUAUUCCUACUCUUUAUCAUUUCCCAACCAACUGUGAGGCUUGUAUGAAGCCCCUGUGGCACAUGUUUAAGCCUCCUCCUGCUUUGGAGUGCCGCCGUUGCCAUAUUAAGUGUCAUAAAGAUCAUAUGGACAAAAAGGAGGAGAUUAUAGCACCUUGCAAAGUAUAUUAUGAUAUUUCAACGGCAAAGAAUCUGUUAUUACUAGCAAAUUCUACAGAAGAGCAGCAGAAGUGGGUUAGUCGGUUGGUGAAAAAGAUACCUAAAAAGCCCCCAGCUCCAGACCCUUUUGCCCGAUCAUCUCCUAGAACUUCAAUGAAGAUACAGCAAAACCAGUCUAUUAGACGGCCAAGUCGACAGCUUGCCCCAAACAAACCUAGAUUGCUUGAUUUGGCAUUUAAAGACUGGGAUUGGUCAUUUGAUGAUGUUGAUGGUGGUGGUGAUGAUGAUGACGAUGUUUUUGAUUUCUGAAGAAAUAAAUGGGCUAACUGCCUUCUAUGAAAGCAGUCAUUAUUCAAGGUGAUCGUAUUCUUCCAGUGAAAACAAGACUGAAAUAUGAUGGCCCAAAAUUUAUUAAAAAGCUAUAUUUUCCUGAGAGACUGAUACAUACACUCAUACAUAUAUGUGUUCCCCUUUUCCCUGUAAUAUAAAUUACAAAUCUGGGCUCCUUUGAAGCAACAGGUUGAACCAACAAUGAUUGGUUGAUAGACUAAGGAUAUAUGCAACUCUUCCAGACUUUUCCAUAAAGCUCUCUCGGCAGUCGCUCACACUACAAUGCACACAAGGAUUGAGAAGAGUUAAAGGCUAAAGAAAACAUCUUUUCUAGCUUCAACAGAGAGGUUUCACCAGCACAUUUACCAGAAGAAUCUGGGAAUGGAUUCCACUACAGUGAUAUUGACUGCAUCUUUAAGAAGUGACCAUUAUACUGUGUAUAUAUAUAUAAACACACACACAUAUAUAUAUAUAUAUAUAGUACUCUAAUACUGCAAGAAGGUUUUUUAAACUUCCCACUUUAUUUUUUAUACACAUUAAUCAGAUAUCAUUACUUGCUGCAGUUGCAACUAUGCACUUGUAUAAAGCCAUAAUGUUGGAGUUUAUAUCACUCAUUCCUGUGUACCUGAUGGAAGUUGCAUGUUCAUGUUUAAGCAGUUACUGUAACAAGAAGUUUAAAGUUAAUUAUAUCAGUUUCCUAAUGCUUCAUGAUAGGCAACUUUACCCAUUUUGAAUGCCUUAAUUUAAUUUUUUUCAAAGUCUCAGCCCUGUCUGUAUUAAAAAACAAAAAAAGCGUUUACCAGCUCUUAGGAUGUAAACUAGCUUUGUGGAAGAUAAAUCGUGCACUAUUUUUACACAUAAAUAGUUAUAUCAAUGUCAGCCUAUUUUGAUUAACAAAUGUUUUUAAAGUAUUAUUGGUUAUAGAAACAAUAAUGGAUGGUGUUGGAACUAAUAUAUCCUUGAUGUCUGUCUAUUAUUCAUUCAACUCUUUUUACAGACCUCAGUAUUAGUCUGUGACUACAAAAUAUUUUAUUUGCUUUAAAUUUGCUGGCUACCCUAGAUGUGUUUUUAUUCCUGGUAAAGACAUUUGUGAUUACAUUUUCACACUUAAGAUUCAAAAUUUUUCCCAAAUAUAAAGAAAACUAAGACAGACUGUAGAUGCAUUUUAAAUAUUUAAAUAUGAUCCUCAGACAUGCAGCUGUGUGUGGCAGUAUUUUAGUACCGGGUUAAGAAAACUGGCAACUGGGAAGAAGUGGCCUCAAAGGCACUUAAUUUGAUUUUUAUUUUUUAAAUGCUGUCAAAGUUACAGUUUACGCAGGACAUUCUUGCCGUAUUCUCAUGAUCCCAGAUAAGUGUGUGUUUUAUACUGCAACAAUAUGCAGCAAUGGUAAGCGUAAAGUUUUUUUUUUGUUUUUGUUUUUUUUUAUAUUAUGAAGUCUUUUAACAGUCUCUCUUUAUAUAAAUACACAGAGUUUGGUAUGAUAUUUAAAUACAUCAUCUGGCCAGGCAUGGUGGCUUACGCCUGUAAUCCUAGCACUUUGGGAGGCCAAGACGGGCGGAUCACCUGAGGUGAGGAGUUCAAGACCAGCCUGCCCAACAUAGUGAAACUCCGUCUCUACCAAUAUACAAAAAUUAGCCGGGCAUGAUGGUGGUGGCCUGUAAUCCCAGCUACUUGGGAGGCUGAGACAGGAGAAUCGCUUGAACCCAGGAGACGGUGGUUGCAGUGAGCGAAGAUCGAGCCACUGCACUCCAGCCUGGGCAGCUGAACAAGACUCCGUCUCAAAAAAAAAAAAAAAAAAAAGUCAUCUAAUAUUUCGAUGAAGGAAAUAGACAUUUUUCAUUGAUUCCCUCUGAUGUCAGUUAGAGAUAUUUAAAAAGUUAGAUCCCCAUAAUAGAUACUAUUGUGGAAACUGAAGAGUAGCUACUGGCCUACUGAUAGACUGAAACUGGUUUUGUUAUUCUUAACGUUCUCCAGUCUGCACUCUGCUGUGCUGUCUGUGCUCAGACUAGACGUGCAUGCCGUUUCCUUUGCAGGUGUGUUCUGCAGCUCUGGUUUUGGGGGAUAGCUCUUUUUUAAGUAAGAUUAAAAAAUGAAAAAUAUAUAAAUUUAUAUAGAAUAAAUAUUUCCAUUCAUUAGAGUUGUUAAAAGGAGACUGAAUUAAUAUUUUAUAUAAAGAUUUUGUUACAUUAUGGGAGGUUCUAUCCUAUUCUGAAUUGGAGAGUAUAUAUAUAUAUAUAUAUAUAUAUAUAUUUUUAAUAAACUUUAUUAAGGUGAAAUAAUUUCAAGUUUACAUAUGAGUAACUGAAAUAUUUGAGUAAAAAAGGCAAAAGUUUAAAUUUGGAAUGCUGUAUAUAUUAGAGAAUAUGGGGAAUCAUGGUGUGACCAACUGUACAAGGAAGAUUCAUAUGAAGGUCUUAGGGGAAAAAGAUAAUUCUGAAGGGUGAAAAAAAAAUCUCUCCCAUGGAGAUUCUUCACAUUAUAUGGUUUGACAUAAGGGUUUAUAAGGUUGUUUGUCCAACUAAUGAAAAUGCGCUUAAUAAAAAAUUCUGACCUUGGGUAAGAAUUCGCUUUUUACCGCAUUGCCGCUUUCAUGUACAUACAUGAGUGCAUGCACCUAUCAAUGUGUUUUCUUCCCAACACUUAUUAAAUAUAAAACAACCUGAUUUUGUGCUCGUUUCUCGUUUUUCUUGAGGCCCUGAAGCUUCCAAGAUAAAUAUAAGACUAAAAUUUGCUUGUUCCUUCACACCUGAUUUCUCCUAGAACCAUAAAUACCUCCUAUGGGGAACUAAGAAAUCAUGAAUACUGGGAUUUUCUUAUUGGAUUUUUUACUUUUGUUUUGUGGGGAUAACGAGACAGAAGUGAAAGGAAAACUGGUGCCGGUAUUACUGUUGAAAUUAAUGUACAGUGAAUGUUUUUAAAGUAUUAAUUUUAAAAAACCAUGUUCUCUAGAAACAAGUUUUAAAAAUCUAUAUGAAAGUUUUAAAAUGUUCCAGCUAACUAAUGGAUAAGCAUACCAGUAAAGCCAAAGUAAAGGUUAGUGCCUUUAAAACUAACCUGUGUUAGAGUUACAUGAAUCUGGCUCUAAAGUAUCUAUUUUGCAUCCAUUUAUAUAUAGAUCUUAAACAGAAAUACUCUAGGUUGCCACACCACAGUUUUAAGAAGUUAUGCUGCUGCUGUUACUCUCUUCUAGGAUUCUGGUGGUAAAGUAGAGAAACUCGGACACUAUAUUAACCUUACUGAAACAUGCUUUAAAUCGUGUCUAAAAUCUGAUUUGAGCAAGUCACUGCCGAGCUUCUGAGUCUGCAUUGACACUGCUACUGACUCACCUCUCCUUCCCUGGAAUAAGGCUUCAGCUUCCCUAUGCUGUGAAGACACCAUUUGUAAGCACUUUGAACAUAAGCACUGUGUGACAGCGCUGGAUAUCAUGCUUGGGGGGGGGCCUCUCCCUGACUCCCAUCCCCAUAAUAAUGAGUUUUGUUUGGAAUUGUAAUAAGUAAUGAACUGCAUGGUUUAGAAAAUUAUAAAUAUUUGAUCAGCUGUCCUCUCUGAAAAAAAUUGCACCCCUUUUUCUUUUUUAAAAUUUUGUUGCAUCUUCGUAGUAAUGUAAUUGUAUUUUAUGCCUGCUUUUUUAUAAAAAAAUAAAAUAAAAUAAAUGGAGACAUAAGCAUUUUCA